CUCCCUUCUUCCGAGCCUCUCCUCUGGCCGCCGCGCGGGAGAGAGGCCGAGAUGGCAGAUGAGAUUGCCAAGGCUCAGGUCGCUCGGCCUGGUGGCGACACGAUCUUUGGGAAGAUCAUCCGCAAGGAAAUACCAGCCAAAAUCAUUUUUGAGGAUGACCGGUGCCUUGCUUUCCAUGACAUUUCCCCUCAAGCACCAACACAUUUUCUGGUGAUACCCAAGAAACAUAUAUCCCAGAUUUCUGUGGCAGAAGAUGAUGAUGAAAGUGUCAUUACUAAGGAAAAACCAGAAAAACCAUUAGGACUUCAACUGCCCAGCUGUUUUCCAAAGUUACUGCAUCAUUUUGUAUCCCACCAGCAAUGAAUGAGCGUUCCAGCUUCUCCGUAUCCUUAUCAACACUUGCUAUUACCUUUUUUUUUUUUUUUUGAGACAGAGUCUUGCUCUGUCGCCCAGGCUGCAGUGCAGUGGCACUCGGCUCACUGCAAGCUCCACCUCCCUGGUUCACACCAUUCUCCUGCCUCAGCCUCCCGAGUAGUGGGACAACAGGCGCCCGCCACCAAGGCUGGCUAAUUUUUUGUAUUUUUAGUAGAGACGGCUUUCACCAUGUUAGUCAGGAUAGUUUCGAUUUCCUGACCUCGUGAUCCGCCCGCCUCGGCCUCCCAAAGUGCUGGGAUUACACGCGUGAGCCACCGUUCCUGGCCUAUUAUAUUCUUAAAGUAAGCUAGAGAAAAGGUUAUUAAGAAAAUCAUAAGGAAGAGAAAAUAUAUUUACUAUUUAUUAAGUCGAGUGAAUCAUAAAGGUCUUCAUCCCUGUCAUCUUCAUGUUGAGUAGGCUGAGGAAGACGAGGGGUUGGUCUAGCUGUAGCUGUCUCAGGGGUGGCAGAGGCAGAAGAAAAUUUGCAUAUGAGUAGACCUGCACGGGUCAAACCCAUGUUGUGCAAGGGUCAGUUGUAUUUACUUGGGGAUACCUUUUUAAAGUGAGACAUUAUUUCUGAAACUUAGAAACUUCAAGGCAUUAAUUUUUAAUUCAAUAUAUUUGUACAAAUCACAGAGUUCAAAGAUUAGAGCGAGUACUUAAUGGUAAAAUACCGUCUUAUAUGCAAUAACAUUAAACCCUCAGAAUACAUUUUUUUCUUUUUUUUUUUUUUUUGAGACGGAGUUUCGUUCUUGUUGCCCAGGCUGGAGUGCAAUGGCACGAUCUCGGCUCACCGCAACCUCUGCCUCCUGGGUACAAGCGAUUCCCCUGCCCUCCUGAGUAGCUGGGAUUACAGGCAUGCCAUCACGCCUGGCUUAUUUGUAUUUUUAGUAGAGAUGGGGUUUCUCCAUGUUGGUCAGGUUAGUCUCGAACUCCCAACCUCACGUGAUCCACCCGCCUCAGCCUUCCAAAGUGCUGGGAUUACAGGUGUCAGCCACCACGCCCAGCCCCAGAAUACAAAUUUUUAACAUUUAGUAUAAUUAGACAGUCAUGGCAUUUUAAGGUCAGAGCUUCUUACUCAAAUGCAGCUCUUUUCUGUAAGGACAAUAAAAUGUUAAUUUUUACUCA